UGUCAAGUUGUUCCUUUUCUGUUGAAACCUGAAUUGAUUGGUUUUGGUUCUUCUGGAAGCAGAUCUUGAGAUAGAAAUCUGAAUCCAAGUUGUGUAUUUGCGAGGUAAUCCCAGGACACACCAGUAGGGGAAUGAAGUGCGCCGUCUAGGAAAGACAGCCAAUAAAGGGCAUGUUUUCAAGCCAGGUCCCGCUGUGGACAAAUGAAGCUUGAUUGUGCUGAGGAAUUCUAGAGCCAGUGUAGCAUACGUAUGUCAGAGUUGUGAUUUUUCCACUGGGGGUUUGGAGGGAGGCUGGAUUUAAGGAAGCUGGAGUCUUCUUAUCAGUAUAUUGUGAGGACUGCCCUCAGGUCUAUAGUGAGCGAGAGCUGCUACUUUUUACUUGGGCAUUCAUUCAAAGUGUUGAAGAAUAACAGCCUCUACCAUCCCUUAUUCACUGGCUCAUCAGCUGUCCCAGGUUUUGCUCUUCUAGGAAAUUGACAAUGGCCCUUCAGCUAUGCUAGGUCUAUAAUGGGAAGUGUCACAGUUCGGUAUUUCUGUUAUGGGUGCCUUUUUACAUCUGCGACCUGGACAGUUUUGCUUUUUGUUUAUUUCAACUUCAGUGAAGUGACUCAGCCACUUAAGAAUGUGCCCGUCAAGGGGUCUGGGCCCCACGGACCAUCUCCAAAAAAAUUCUAUCCCCGUUUCACUCGAGGCCCAAGUCGAGUGCUCGAGCCACAGUUCAAAGCAAACAAAAUUGACGAUGUGAUAGACAGUCGUGUUGAAGAUCCAGAAGAAGGCCACUUGAAAUUCUCUUCUGAAUUAGGUAUGAUUUUUAAUGAACGCGAUCAAGAGUUGAGAGACUUGGGCUAUCAGAAACAUGCUUUUAAUAUGCUUAUCAGUGACCGCUUGGGCUACCACAGAGAUGUGCCAGACACAAGGAAUGCAGCAUGUAAAGAAAAGUUCUACCCACCUGACCUGCCAGCUGCUAGUGUUGUUAUCUGUUUCUAUAAUGAAGCGUUUUCUGCCUUGCUUCGGACAGUGCACAGUGUCAUAGACCGCACGCCAGCACACCUGCUUCAUGAGAUCAUCCUUGUGGAUGAUGAUAGUGACUUUGAUGAUUUGAAAGGAGAACUAGAUGAAUAUGUCCAAAAAUACCUCCCUGGAAAAAUUAAAGUCAUAAGAAAUACAAAGCGUGAGGGGUUGAUUCGAGGGAGAAUGAUUGGCGCGGCCCACGCGACAGGAGAAGUCCUUGUGUUCCUGGACAGCCACUGUGAAGUGAAUGUGAUGUGGCUGCAGCCCUUGCUGGCCGCCAUCCGUGAGGACCGGCACACCGUGGUGUGCCCAGUGAUUGACAUCAUCAGCGCCGACACGCUGGCCUACAGCUCGUCCCCUGUCGUCCGCGGAGGGUUCAACUGGGGACUGCACUUCAAAUGGGAUCUUGUCCCCCUUUCUGAGCUAGGACGAGCGGAGGGAGCCACUGCACCAAUAAAGUCACCAACAAUGGCUGGAGGUUUGUUUGCCAUGAACAGACAGUAUUUCCAUGAACUUGGACAGUAUGAUAGUGGCAUGGAUAUCUGGGGAGGAGAAAAUUUGGAAAUAUCAUUUCGGAUCUGGAUGUGUGGCGGUAAGCUCUUCAUCAUCCCUUGCUCUAGAGUAGGACACAUUUUCCGAAAAAGGCGACCAUAUGGAUCUCCCGAAGGCCAGGACACCAUGACACACAACUCUUUGCGGCUGGCACAUGUCUGGUUGGAUGAAUACAAGGAGCAGUAUUUUUCCUUAAGACCUGACCUGAAGACGAAAAGCUAUGGCAAUAUCAGUGAGCGUGUGGAACUGAGAAAGAAGUUGGGCUGUAAAUCAUUUAAAUGGUAUUUGGAUAAUGUAUACCCAGAGAUGCAGAUAUCUGGGUCCCACGCCAAACCCCAACAACCCAUUUUUGUCAAUAGAGGGCCAAAACGACCCAAAGUCCUUCAACGUGGAAGGCUCUAUCACCUCCAGACCAACAAAUGCCUGGUGGCCCAGGGCCGCCCAAGUCAGAAGGGAGGUCUCGUGGUGCUUAAGGCCUGUGACUACAGUGACCCAAAUCAGAUCUGGAUCUAUAAUGAAGAGCAUGAAUUGGUUUUAAAUAGUCUCCUUUGUCUAGAUAUGUCAGAGACUCGCUCAUCAGACCCGCCACGGCUCAUGAAAUGCCACGGGUCAGGAGGAUCCCAGCAGUGGACCUUUGGGAAAAACAAUCGGCUAUACCAGGUGUCGGUUGGACAGUGCCUGAGAGCAGUGGAUCCCCUGGGUCAGAAGGGCUCUGUCGCCAUGGCGAUCUGCGAUGGCUCCUCUUCACAGCAGUGGCAUUUGGAAGGUUAAGGUGGAUGCUGUGGUGGGAACGUUGCUUCAUCAGGCGUUGCCUCCGGUGUGGAGUUUGGGGCUUUAGGAAAGCCUGGGUUGGGUGGAGCAGAACCAUCUUGGAGAAGAUGACAGUUCCCUGUCCUCCCGGAGAUGCCUGGGUGUGUUAGCAGAGGUGACACGUGUCUGACAGAGACGGGAGCUCUGAGUGUCCACGGGUGAAGAAGUGAGUGUCCACGGGUGAAGAAGUGAGUAUGUUUCACCUGGACAUUAAGGUGAUGUUUGAGCUGCUGUUAAGGAAUUUCUUGCUUAUAGAGGCAAACCACAGUAUCAUUUUAACUCUAGAAUUGGGCUUGUACAGAAGGAUAAAACCCAGGAAAAUGGAUAUUUCUAUUCAGAUUUAUUUAUGCCUCUUUUUAAUCCCCUUUAAUGAUGCAGUGGUUUUUAUCUGAUCAGGAACUUGUCAUGAUUUCCUUUCUUAGACUUCAUAGGAGAUAGUGCUUUAAAAAAAAAAAAAACUUCUAUUAUUUGUUUAGUAUGUUGUAAGUAGAUCAUUUUAAAAAACUGAAUCUAUAUUAUGUUUAACUUCAGAAGGCAUCAUUUAUAAGACAGUAUGGCAGUUAAUUAUAAAAUUAUUUUGAUGAAUUAUGAUACAAUCUACAUAAUAAAGAAUCCUUUUGAUUA